CCUUGCUGUUGCCGCCGCCGCAGCUGCUGCCGCGGUUGGUGGGGUUGGGUGAGAGGAGGAGCUGUCGCGGACCCUGUAGAGUCGGUCUCUGUUGCUCUUUUUGCCUGAGGAGUCUUCCAUCCUACGUCGAGCUCUGACUCCCGUGCUGUCGAGAGGGAGUCCCCGGGGACACCUCGGCACGCAGCGGAGAUGCCUCUUUUUGCCACCAAUCCCUUCGAUCAGGAUGUUGAGAAAGCAACCAGCGAGAUGAAUACUGCUGAGGACUGGGGCCUCAUUUUGGAUAUCUGUGAUAAAGUUGGUCAGUCUCGCACUGGACCUAAGGAUUGUCUUCGGUCUAUUAUGAGAAGAGUGAACCACAAAGAUCCUCACGUUGCUAUGCAGGCUUUGACUCUUCUAGGAGCAUGUGUAUCAAACUGUGGCAAAAUUUUUCAUUUAGAAGUAUGUUCAAGAGAUUUUGCUAGUGAAGUAAGCAACGUAUUAAAUAAGGGUCAUCCUAAAGUAUGUGAAAAAUUAAAGGCUCUUAUGGUUGAAUGGACAGAUGAAUUUAAGAAUGAUCCACAGCUUAGUCUAAUAUCAGCAAUGAUUAAGAACCUUAAGGAACAAGGAGUUACGUUCCCAGCUAUUGGCUCUCAGGCUGCAGAACAAGCAAAAGCAAGCCCAGCUCUUGUAGCCAAGGAUCCUGGUACUGUGGCUAACAAAAAAGAAGAAGAAGAUUUAGCAAAAGCCAUUGAGUUGUCUCUCAAGGAACAAAGGCAGCAGUCAACCACCCUUUCCACUUUGUAUCCAAGCACAUCCAGUCUCUUAACUAACCACCAACAUGAAGGCCGAAAAGUUCGUGCUAUAUAUGACUUUGAAGCUGCUGAAGACAAUGAACUUACUUUUAAAGCUGGAGAAAUUAUUACAGUUCUUGAUGACAGUGAUCCUAACUGGUGGAAAGGUGAAACCCAUCAAGGCAUAGGGUUAUUUCCUUCUAAUUUUGUGACUGCAGAUCUCACUGCUGAACCAGAAAUGAUUAAAACAGAGAAGAAGACGGUACAAUUUAGUGAUGAUGUUCAGGUAGAGACAAUAGAACCAGAGCCGGAACCAGCCUUUAUUGAUGAAGAUAAAAUGGACCAGUUGCUACAGAUGCUGCAAAGUACAGACCCCAGUGAUGAUCAGCCAGACCUACCAGAGCUGCUUCAUCUUGAAGCAAUGUGUCACCAGAUGGGACCUCUCAUUGAUGAAAAGCUGGAAGAUAUUGAUAGAAAACAUUCAGAACUCUCAGAACUUAAUGUGAAAGUGAUGGAGGCCCUUUCCUUAUAUACCAAGUUAAUGAACGAAGAUCCGAUGUAUUCCAUGUAUGCAAAGUUACAGAAUCAGCCAUAUUAUAUGCAGUCAUCUGGUGUUUCUGGUUCUCAGGUGUAUGCAGGGCCUCCUCCAAGUGGUGCCUACCUGGUUGCAGGGAACGCGCAGAUGAGCCACCUCCAGAGCUACAGUCUUCCCCCGGAGCAGCUGUCUUCUCUCAGCCAGGCAGUGGUCCCACCAUCCGCAAACCCAGCCCUUCCUAGUCAGCAGACUCAGGCCGCUUACCCAAACCGCUCCCCAGGGGACCUCAUGAAGCCCGGUGAUUCUGAAUGCCGUGGAUCUGCCGAGGAUUCCCAGAUGCGUAUUUCUCCUCCGUACUUCCCCACAGGACAGCAGGCUUGAAUAGCUGAUUGCCUAUGCAGGACAACAGGCUUGAAUAGCUGACUGCCUAUGCAUUCUCUUUGCUUGCCAGUUUUUUGGACAUCAAACUUGACAGAUCCAAGAUUAUUACUUUGAUCUUCCCCACACCCCUCCCACCCCCGAGUCUACUAUGGUCCCAUCAUAGUAUUCUGAAAAUCAGUGAAUGGCCACUCUACCAGUUAUUUCUACCAGUUUUUAGGUUCUAAACCUCAGGCAUUCUGGACUCUUCUGUUCAUUAUCAUAUUUUGAAGGCAUUAUCUUCAAAAUCUAUCUAGACUCUGACCCUUUCUCCCAUCUCCACCAUUACUGCCGUGGCUCUUCUGCUGGUCGGCUCUCUCCUGGUGGAUCGUAAUAACCUGCAGUCAGCUAUCCUGGUCCAGAGGGAGCCCGUUAAACCCUGUGGAAUCUUAUCACGCUUCUGCUCAGAACGAGCCAGUGUCUUUCUGUCUCACUCAGAGUGUAAGCUACAGUCCUUAUUGUGGCCAUCAGGUGCUGUGUGUUCUCCAGCCCCCUCCCCACCACCGCAGUCCUGCCGGUGAUCUUAGCUGCUCUCCCCUCGGCACCCCCUGCGGCCCCCUCUGCCGCAGCACUCGUGGCCUGCUGUUCCUUGAACAUGCUUGGUGUUUUCUCUCCUCAAAGGCUUCUUUCUGUUUACCUGAAAUGUACUUUCCUAGGGAAUCUAUCUGGCUCACUCGCUUACUUUUUCCACAUCUUUGCUUAAGUAUUGCCUUAUUGGAGAGGCACCCUACCAUAAACUAGAAUCCCUUGCCCCAGCUGCUCUUUGUCCUCCGUAUUGGGCUUUGUUUUUGUUCUUACCAGUUAGAACCACUUGACACACGAUACAUGUGUUUGUUACCCUUUUCUACCACUAGAACAGACGCUCCAUGGUGGUAUAGACUUAUUUCCGCAAACCACCCCCCCCAACUUUUUUUACACAAUGGUUAAAUAACACACAUAUUUUUAAUGCAAUGCCUGAUAUCACAAAGCCUAAAAUAACAAUGUUUGGCACAUUAUAGCUGUUUAGUAAAAGGUUAUUAAAUGAAUUGACUAUAUGAAUGAAUGCUUAGUAAAUAGCUUUUCCAUUUAUCUGUAGUUGCUCUAUAAAUCAGUAUUGAUGUAAUUGAGUGUUUUUCUUCCUCCACAGUACAAUGGUCAGUUCCGUUCAAGGAAACACAUAUCCCAGCCAGGCGCCAGUAUAUAGUCCUCCUCCUGCCGCUACUGCUGCUGCUGCAACUGCCGAUGUCACUCUGUACCAGAAUGCAGGACCUAAUAUGCCCCAGGUGCCAAACUAUAACUUAACAUCAUCAACUCUGCCUCAGCCCGGAGGCAGCCAACAGCCACCUCAGCCACAGCAACCAUAUUCUCAGAAGGCUCUGCUAUAGGACCCGGUGUUCCUCUUGGUGGCAGAUACCUGCUAAAUGCCACUGACAAUGUUAUGAGAUUCAUUACUAUCUUAAGAUGUGUUUAUCCUCAGCUUAUAGGAAUCUCUCCAGGUCAACAGGUUCAAAUAUUCAAGAAGGUAGAACUCUCCUCAAUUUACACUGACUUUUUAGAGGUUCUUCCCCCCCCGCCCCUGCAGAGGAAUGAAACUACUUACAACAUUUAAUUCCUUUCAUAAUAUGAAAGAAUUGAUACAAGGCUAUUUGUCUCGUAAACCUGGUCUGCAGAAAGUCAAACUUACAAAAACUGUUGUGACAAAUGUUAUGUACAUAUAUUGAUAUGUAACUGCAUUAGUGGCCAUUUUGAAUCACAGUGGUGAUCGUGUGAAUAUAUUUAACACUGUGUUAAAUUAAUUUACGUUGCUAUUUUAUUUUAAUCAUAAACAACUACCAUGUUUCUUAAUGUUUUGUGUAAAUUUAAGGUAAUUAUACUAUCCUUUUAAACUUCAAGAAAACAAAGUUGUUAGCGUAUUUACAUGAAGGCGCAUUAUGUUGUCGUGUGUUUCAGUUUCACAUUAAACUGAACCUUUUACUAAUUGUGAGCUAAAGAGAUAUAUAUAUAUAUGUGUGUGUAUAUAUAUAUAUCUACAUGUCUUUCUGUAGCCUCUGCAUACUACUGGCUGUCAUCACACCAGCGUACAGUAGCUAAAUUUUUGGUGCAAUUAUAGCAAAUGAUAAUGUUCCCUUUUGAACUUUUACAUUUUGGCAUGACAUUUCAGAGUAUUGUGGGACCAUGAGACAAAAUUAAGUACGAUCACAUUCUUUAUUUCUCAUUUUAAAGAAAUGAUGUUGGUUUACCUUUUCCUAGUUGAAGAUAGUAAUUAGGUUUCUAAGCUGUAUACUGUGUUUAUUGGUGGCAGUGACACCAAAGAUAGAGGCAAUGGAUAGAAAUUUUUAAACUGGAAAGAAAACCUGAAUUACACUACAUUUUCGAAGUCUCUUGUAAUUAUUUGGGAUAUCAACAAAAUUUGAUUCGUCUGUCUAAUCCCUUGCUAGUAUUUUAAAUAUGUCUUUAACACAUUGUAUCCUUUAAUUCUUCAUUAAAAUGGAAAUAAGUAGAUGUUUCAAAGUAA